GCAGAGUCUGCGGACCCGGCGCCGAGGCGGCCACCCGAGACGCGGCGCGCACGCUCCGGCCUGCGCAGCCCGGCCCGGCCAUGGCGGCCCCCCGCCCGUCUCCCGCGAUCUCCGUUUCGGUCUCGGCUCCGGCUUUUUACGCCCCGCAGAAGAAGUUCGGCCCUGUGGUGGCCCCAAAGCCCAAAGUGAAUCCCUUCCGGCCCGGGGACAGCGAGCCUCCCCCGGCACCCGGGGCCCAGCGCGCACAGAUGGGCCGGGUGGGCGAGAUUCCCCCGCCGCCCCCGGAAGACUUUCCCCUGCCUCCACCUCCCCUUGCUGGGGAUGGCGACGAUGCAGAGGGUGCUCUGGGAGGUGCCUUCCCGCCGCCCCCUCCCCCGAUCGAGGAAUCAUUUCCCCCUGCGCCUCUGGAGGAGGAGAUCUUCCCUUCCCCGCCGCCUCCUCCGGAGGAGGAGGGAGGGCCUGAGGCCCCCAUACCGCCCCCACCACAGCCCAGGGAGAAGGUGAGCAGUAUUGAUUUGGAGAUCGACUCUCUGUCCUCACUGCUGGAUGACAUGACCAAGAAUGAUCCUUUCAAAGCCCGGGUGUCAUCUGGAUAUGUGCCCCCACCAGUGGCCACUCCAUUCAGUUCCAAGUCCAGUACCAAGCCUGCAGCCGGGGGCACAGCACCCCUGCCUCCUUGGAAGUCCCCUUCCAGCUCCCAGCCUCUGCCCCAGGUUCCGGCUCCGGCUCAGAGCCAGACACAGUUCCAUGUUCAGCCCCAGCCCCAGCCCAAGCCUCAGGUCCAACUCCAUGUCCAGUCCCAGACCCAGCCUGUGUCUUUGGCUAACACCCAGCCCCGAGGGCCCCCAGCCUCAUCUCCGGCUCCAGCCCCUAAGUUUUCUCCAGUGACUCCUAAGUUUACUCCUGUGGCUUCCAAGUUCAGUCCUGGAGCCCCAGGUGGAUCUGGGUCACAACCAAAUCAAAAAUUGGGGCACCCCGAAGCUCUUUCUGCUGGCACAGGCUCCCCUCAACCUCCCAGCUUCACCUAUGCCCAGCAGAGGGAGAAGCCCCGAGUGCAGGAGAAGCAGCACCCCGUGCCCCCACCGGCUCAGAACCAAAACCAGUUCAGGAAAUAAGAUCGUCCAAUUUCUGGUGACGAAGAUGACCCUGAUGGUCAUCUAGUCCAAGCAUCCAGAGUCCACUGAUAGUGUUGAUGUCUACCUACACUCGGACACAGCAUAGGAAGAAAUGCCAAGGGCCAGUGAGCUUUGCAGAAUCCUGUGAGUCACAGGCACUCAGACCAGGGAGUCAACUCGGGGAGUCAAAUUAGGAAAGGCUUCGAAGGAUGGGCAGGACGUAAGAAUCCAGAGAGGAGAGGGAUGUUUGGAGAACAGAAAGUGGAAGGUUCCUGUAGGAAAAUGAUAGAGCUAUACUUGGAGAGGCAAGCGGGGCUGGAGGGUGUAGGAGGUGAAGUGGCUCACCCAAGGAGCUCUUGAGCACUGGAGAGGCAUUCAUGAUUUUUGAGUAGGUGUGGGGUGGGUCAGGAGGGCUGGUGAAAGCAGUGUUUUUGGAAGCUUUCUGGAAAGUUUCACCAGCAGAGAUGUGUAUUCGAGGGAGGUCAGUGAUGGGUGUGAAUUCACUCUUGGGCAAUAGUAAUGUUAGCUGCAAUGAAAAUUAAACCGUGCAUGUGAGAGCUGUGUGCUAGAGCUGUUGGGAAGGCACAGCCUCCAGGACUUAGCAAGGGAUGAGCAAUUGGAAGACAAGGGUGAGGGGAAGAGGGAAAAAAAAGUCUCCAGCACGAUUUGGAGAUGGGGUGUGGGCGGAUGGCAGGAUUGCUGACAAAAUAGAGAAGUCCAGAAGGGGAAAUGGUUUGGACGGGAAGAGGAGGGGUCCAGCUGUCAACGUUUUGAGCAACAGGUCCCAGGAGGACUUUCAGCUGGGGCCGUCAUUCAGCUAGAAAUCCAGGGCUAGGUUUCAGGAGAGGGCCAGAGAUGUCUAGCAUGGUAGUGGGGCACAGUGACACUGUGACGCUGGAGGGUCAGGGUCGGAGCGGAGGAGCUUCCCAGGGAGUGCAGACAGCGGGGACCAGGAGGUGCGGGAAGAAGAGUCAGGAGGAGAGUCAGGGUGCACUUGGAGAAGAGAGCUGAGCUCCUCAGUGGGGUAUUUGAGGGAGUGAGGACUCAAGGCUAGAGAUUAGACUGUUGGGAAAUCAUCAGCGGUCUUGGGAUGGCCUGUUUGUGCCCUGUGGUGGGAACACAAUGUGAGGAGUUGAGGAGAGAGUGGGUGGUGAGAAGUGGGGCUGCUGGUGUAGCCUGGUCUUAAAGGACUAAGGGAAGGACUGUGUGUCAGUGGUGUGUGUGUGUGUAUAUAUACACAUAUGUGAAUAUAUGAGUGGCGUGUGUGUGUGUGUUAGUGUGUGG